GGGUUCAUGGGUUCCUGGGUCUGUGGGUGGCUGGUUCCUGGGUUUGUGGGUCUGUGGGUCCCUGGGUCCGUGCGUUCCUGGGUUCAUGGGUUCCUGGAUCUGUGGGUUCCUGGUUCCUGGGUCCGUGGGUCCGUGGGUUCUUGGGUUCCUGGGUCUGUGGGUACCUGGGUCUUUGGGUCCCUAGGUCCCUGGGUUCCUGGAUCUGUGGGUUCCUGGGUUCGUGGGUUCGUGGGUUCUGGGUCUGUGGGUCCAUGGGUUCCUGGGUUCUGAGGUUCAUGGGUUCCUGGGUGCCUGUGUUCACUGCUGCUCGCUUUGCUCUGUGUCACAGGCAGGCUGCUGGGGAGCCAUCCUCACUUCCUGUACCUCAACAGGCUCCAGCUCUUUUCCCUGCCCCAGCCCUGAAAUCAGCCGUUUCUAUACAGACUGUGAGGCCUGUUUUUAAAAUAAAAUCCUAGUUAUUAUUUUUUCAAGUUAUAGUGUGGCUGCUGUUGCCUUUCUAGGGUUGUGUGUGUGCUUUGUGCAAUCAGGAGGGUUUGGAAGGUGGGUGUGCAGCCCCUCGUGGUGCACGGUGUGAAGGGAGCUGGCCCCUCACCUUGCAGGAGUGGUUGGUGGGAUUAGGGAGGGAGGCUGGCUUGUCAGCCAUAGAGCCCCAUCCUGUGAGGGCUCUGAGGCUGGGAGAGAGGUGAGUCCGGGCCGUGGCUGUGAGCUGGUGGCUCUGACGCUGGGACAGAGGUGAGUCCCGGCUGUGGCUGUGGCUGUGAGCUGGUGGCUCUGACGCUGGGACAGAGGUGAGUCCGGGCCGUGGCUGUGGCUGUGAGCUGGGGGCUCUGACGCUGGGACAGAGGUGAGUCCCGGCUGUGGCUGUGGCUGUGAGCUGGUGGCUCUGACGCUGGGACAGAGGUGAGUCCGGGCCGUGGCUGUGAGCUGGUGGCUCUGACGCUGGGACAGAGGUGAGUCCGGGCCGUGGCUGUGAGCUGGGGGCUCUGACGCUGGGACAGAGGUGAGUCCGGGCCGUGGCUGUGGCUGUGAGCUGGUGGCUCUGACGCUGGGACAGAGGUGAGUCCGGGCUGUGGCUGUGGCUGUGAGCUGGGGGCUCUGACGGUGGGACAGAGGUGAGUCCGGGCUGUGGCUGUGAGCUGGUGGCUCUGACGCUGGGACAGAGGUGAGUCCGGGCCAUGGCUGUGGCUGUGAGCUGGUGGCUCUGACGCUGGGACAGAGGUGAGUCCGGGCCGUGGCUGUGGCUGUGAGCUGGUGGCUCUGACGCUGGGACAGAGGUGAGUCCGGGCCGUGGCUGUGGCUGUGAGCUGGGGGCUCUGACGCUGGGACAGAGGUGAGUCCCGGCUGUGGCUGUGAGCUGGGGGCUCUGACGCUGGGACAGAGGUGAGUCUGGGCUGUGGCUGUGAGCUGGCACCCCAGUUACUGGUGGUUUUUCCCCAGCUGACAUCGACCAGCGUGGGGUGUGCAGUGUGGCUGGCUCUGAUUUGUGCUCCUUAGUUUGAGACAAUUUGAAUGGAGCCACUGCUGUGGAGAGGCCUCCUUCUGAAGCAUCACAAGUGGGCCCGGCUGACCCUAGCCCAGUGCACGACACCCCUCUUGGAGUCUGGGGUUCUUGGCUGUGGGCUGGAGAUGACAGUGGUGGCUGCCGAGGGUGGUGGGAGUGGUCAGUGCUGAGCACGCGAUUUCAGAUCCAGUGAGCCAGGCGGGCACAGCCUUUAGCUGAUGUGGUGUGUCCCCUGGCCUGGAACAGCCCCAUGGGUGGGUGGCACCCGUCAGGACCUGUGCACAGACCCUGCCUGGGUUUGGUCUGCCCAGUCCCCUGGACCUGGCAGCAGCGGGGCUGUGCCUGGUGACGGGAAGGCUCUGAGCCAGGCUGGGUGGCCCACUGUGCGCGUCGCUGCUGUGUUGGUGGUGGCGCCUUUGCCCUGGCCCUCAUUCAGGAAGAUGCUGGCUUUUGGGCUCUAGGGAAGUGCAUGUUGGUUUCUGUCGAGAGCGGUUGUGUGUGUACAUUUUAAGCGUGGAACGCAGGUAUCGAACCGUGUUGAAACCUUUCCAGCAUUGGCAGAAGUGUGCGUGUGAGUCUCCUUUGCCCUUUUACUUUACUGGCAGGUGUAGUGAACUUGGAUGCCGCCUGCCUUCCUAGCAUGGCCCACGUGGCCGGGCGGUCCUUCUGAUGGGGCGGCUCACGUGGCUCCCACGUGCCAGGCUUUUGGGGCAGAUGCUCCUGAGCGGUGCUGCCUACGGGUUGCCUUCAUUGGUGGUGGUGAGGCCUGGGCUUUGGCGUCCUGUCCGCCCUUAAUCCUUGCCUAGGAGCAGUCUGUGGGCCCCAGAAGACUGGCCGGAAACUGAAGCCGGGCGGCAGCUGAGGACGCACACCCUGGAGGUUGUGUGGACGUUCCGUCACUGCUGUCUUAAUUCCCAGGCACUCUUCUUUUUCUCUGGAAGUUCCUUUUUGAGGGUGUCCUGGUGUUCAUGGAGGUGCCGUAUCACUCCGAGGGCAGAGGGCUGCUGCUGAGGAAGGCCUUGCCCUCUCACCUAGCACUCUUCUCCAAGUUGCUGGUUUUGCUUGUUUGCACCUUGUCUGUUUUGGCCUCUGUUGGGUCUGAACUAGGUGUCCUUGGCAGCUGCUCACACCCAACAGUGGGACCCUGAGAAGGGUCAAAGCCGGGGCAGUUUGGGGACACGCUGGGUGCAGGGCCACCUUGCUGGGCACCUCGGCUGGUUGGUGUCUGUUGGGAGCAGCCCUGGGGCCGCCCCGCAGCCUCUGCCUGCAGUACAGACGGAUCUGCCCACUCCUGAGGCUGGAGAGCUCAGAGCCUGAAAGACCCCCUGAGCCCUCGCCCUUCCUCCGCCGGCCCCUUGCUGUCAGCACGCCAGGUGCAGACCCUGGCAGGCUUCCUGUGCCCCAGCUUCAGUGUGGAGCGCUUGCCUAGCUGGCUGGCAUGGGAGCGGGAGGGGUGUUUGGCCACUUGGAGCAGAAGGGGGUGGGUAGUCAGAGUUUCUGUGUUCCUGGCUUGAUAUUGGCUUUCCAGCAGCUUCCCAGCUUCCAGAAUGUCCUUGCCAUCAUCUCCCAUCCUGUUUCCUCUUUUUUGGAGCAGAGGCCUGGGGUGGCCUAUCUUCUUCUUUCAGUUGAGGCUUCCGGGGCGGGUGGGUCUAAUGUGUGUCUUUGCCUUUAGCCAGAAGACCACCGUGAUUAGAUUUUCCAGAAGAGAACUCGCGUGGUAGUUUUGAAAAUGGGAGGGUGUUUGUGAGGUGGGAUAUCAGAAAUACUUUAUACAGAGGGGACCCAACAUGUAGCAGAAACAUCAACAAAAUGGUUUUGCGUAUAAUCACAUGAUGAUUUCUCUCUUCUGAGAAACAGGCACAAAUCCUGAAGAGCCCGUGGGCGUGGACUGCUCAUCUGUAAAGAAAGUGGAGACAUGACCUUGAGAUUUGGCUGACCCAGCAAUGCUGGGGCCUUCGCAAGUCUGAUGUUCCAGGACUCCAGUGCCUGUUGGUGUGGACGGAGGACACGGGGCCCCGACCAUGGUCACACUCAUCACUGAGAAGCUGCAGAGCCAGAGCCUGGACGACCUCACCUGCAAGGCGGAGGCUGGCCCGUUGCAGUAUUCUGCGGAAACCCUGAACAAGAGCGGUCGUCUGUUCCCUUUGGAGCUCAACGACCAGAGUCCCUGGAAGGUCUUCAGUGGAGGACCGCCCGUCAGAAGCCAGGCAGCCACGGGCCCUGAUUUCUCCUUCCUGCCGGGCCUGUCUGCUGCCGCUCACACCAUGGGUCUUCAGUGGCAGCCACAGUCCCCGCGCCCAGGCGCAGGCCUGGGUGCAGCCAGCACCGUGGACCCCAGUGAAAGCACAGGCUCGUCCACGGCCCCACCGACCAAGCGGCAUUGCCGGUCCUUGUCAGAACCCGAGGAGCUUGUGCGCUGCCGGUCCCCCUGGCGCCCCGGCAGCUCCAAGGUCUGGACUCCAGUCUCCAAGAGGCGGUGCGACAGCGGCGGGAGUGCCACGCGGCAGGGAAGCCCCGGCGCCGUCCUGCCGAGGAGUGCUGUGUGGUCGACCGGUCCCACCUCGCCCGCCACGCCCCGGCCGUCCUCCGCCAGCGGCGGCUUCGUGGACAGCAGCGAGGGCAGUGCGGGCUCAGGCCCGCUCUGGUGUUCCGCGGAGUCCUGCUUGCCCUCCACGAGGCGCCGCCCGUCCCUCUCACAGGAGCGACUCGCGGGUGCGGGCACUCCCCUGCCCUGGGCCAGCAGCAGCCCCACGUCCACGCCUGCGCUGGGCGGGCGCCGUGGGCUGCUCCGGUGCCGCUCACAGCCUUGCGUGCUCAGUGGGAAGAGGAGCCGGCGCAAACGGAGGCGUGAGGAGGACGCCAGGUGGACACGCCCAUCCUUGGACUUCCUGAAAAUGACCCAGACUUUAAAAAAUUCAAAAAGCCUUUGCUCCCUCAAUUACGAAGAUGACGAUGAGGAUGACACCCCAGUGAAGACGGUUCUGUCCUCCCCAUGUGACUCCCGGGGCCUCCCUGGCAUCACCAUGCCUGGCUGCAGCCAGAGGGGCCUCAGGACCAGCCCUGUCCACCCCAACCUGUGGGCCUCUAGGGAGUCGGUGACCAGUGAUGGCUCCCGCAGGAGCAGCGGGGACCCCCGUGAUGGGGACAGUGUCGGGGAGGAGGGCGUCUUCCCCCGGGCCCGCUGGGAGCUGGACCUGGAGCAGAUCGAGAACAACUGAGGCUGGUGGGGGCUGGUCGGGGCCAUGGCUGCCGCCUGCACCUGCCCUGGGGCACAGAGUAGGUUUCCUGUGAGCUGGUCGGGGCCACGGCCCGGCACCUGCCCUGGGGCACAGAGUAGGUUUCCUGUGAGCUGGUCGGGGCCACGGCUGCCGCCGGCACCUGCCCUGGGGCACAGAGUAGGUUUCCUGUGAGCUGGUCGGGGCCACGGCUGCCGCCGGCACCUGCCCUGGGGCACAGAGUAGGUUUCCUGUGAGCUGGUCGGGGCCACGGCUGCCACCGGCACCUGCCCUGGGGCACAGAGUAGGUUUCCUGUGAGCUGGUCGGGGCCACGGCUGCCGCCUGCACUGCCCUGGGGCACAGACUAGGUUUCCUGUGAGCUGGUCGGGGCCAUGGCUGCUGCCUGCACCUGCCCCAGGGCACAGAGUAGGUUUCCUGUGAGCUGGUCGGGGCCAUGGCUGCCGCCUGCACCUGCCCCGGGGCACAGAGUAGGUUUCCUGUGAGCUGGUCGGGGCCAUGGCUGCCACCGGCACCUGCCCUGGGGCACAGAGUAGGUUUCCUGUGAGUUGGUCGGGGCCACGGCUGCCGCCUGCACUGCCCUGGGGCACAGACUAGGUUUCAUGUGAGCUGGUCGGGGCCAUGGCUGCUGCCGGCACCUGCCCUGGGGCACAGAGUAGGUUUCGUGUUGCUUGGAACAUUAAGGCGUAAUUUUGAUUCAGUUUUUCCUAAAGAAGCAUUUUGCAUUUUUAUGGCUUUUGCAGUUCGGGAGAAAGCUUCUCUAUUUUGGAUGCAUUUCAGAAGGGCGUUCUAUUAAACAUGAAUCUGCAAACAGAUUAACAUGCGUCUGUGUUCCCCACGAAAGGCCUGCUGUGCAGGGCGCCUUGUGUGCUUUAGUUGCUAGGAAACCCCGGGCGUUGGUGGUCAGAGUCCCACUGGCCCCGUGUGUCCCCCCCUCCCGACGGGUCACGGUGCUUGGGGCUUGCGCAUGGGCAUCUGUGCCCAUGAACCUUGUCACCCACGUGCCAGUGAACCGCCAGCUUGUGGCCGCCUGGUUUUCCACCGGUGGCAGUGAUGGCCUUUGGGGCAGACCAAGGUGCCAUGAGUCCCUGCUUCCCGUGGCCUGGGAGGGCCCUUGCACCUUCAGGUGGGGUGUAGUGCCAGACCUCUGGGAAGGCUGUCCUGCCGGCAGCACCCGUCAGCACCCACUCUGUGAAUUUAAUACAAGGCCUUUGCUUUGUGCAUACGACUUCUGAUUAAUUUUCGUUUCCACCAUCUGAAGUGGGCCUGGCUGCGCCUCAGGCCUCUGGUCUCUGGCUCAGAACCAGACAAGGCAAGGGAUUUCCUGUUUUUCAUUCUUGCACUUUUAAUAAAAUCGUAGGGGUUUCGAGUUUGCGAUAGCAAAAGAAAACAUUAA